CCCUCUGCUCCCAGCCUUUGCUGGGCGCCAGACCCGGCUUUGCCGUCCGGCUAUUAGCCUACUGUGGCUAGUCACCCCCGGGGUCCCGGCCUUCUCGGGCUGGGGCCGCCGCCACCGCGGCAGGACGGGGAGGCGGGCCAUGGCGUCCUGCGUGGGGAGCCGGACCCUAAGCAAGGAUGAUGUGAACUACAAAAUGCAUUUCCGGAUGAUCAACGAGCAGCAAGUGGAGGACAUCACCAUUGACUUCUUCUACCGGCCGCAUACCAUCACCCUGCUCAGCUUCACCAUCGUCAGCCUCAUGUACUUCGCCUUUACCAGGGAUGACUCUGUUCCAGAAGACAACAUCUGGAGAGGCAUCCUCUCUGUUAUUUUCUUCUUUCUUAUCAUCAGUGUGUUAGCUUUCCCCAAUGGUCCGUUCACUCGACCUCAUCCAGCCUUAUGGCGAAUGGUUUUUGGACUCAGUGUGCUCUACUUCCUGUUCCUGGUAUUCCUACUCUUCCUGAAUUUCGAGCAGGUUAAAUCUCUAAUGUAUUGGCUAGAUCCAAAUCUUCGAUACGCCACAAGGGAAGCAGAUGUCAUGGAGUAUGCUGUGAACUGCCAUGUGAUCACCUGGGAGAGGAUUAUCAGCCACUUUGAUAUUUUUGCAUUUGGACAUUUCUGGGGCUGGGCCAUGAAGGCCUUGCUGAUCCGUAGUUACGGUCUCUGCUGGACAAUCAGUAUUACCUGGGAGCUGACUGAGCUCUUCUUCAUGCAUCUCCUCCCCAAUUUUGCCGAGUGCUGGUGGGAUCAAGUCAUUCUGGACAUCCUGUUGUGCAAUGGCGGUGGCAUUUGGCUGGGCAUGGUCGUUUGCCGGUUUUUAGAGAUGAGGACUUACCACUGGGCAAGCUUCAAGGACAUUCAUACCACCACCGGGAAGAUCAAGAGAGCUGUUCUGCAGUUCACUCCUGCUAGCUGGACCUAUGUUCGAUGGUUUGACCCCAAAUCUUCUUUUCAGAGAGUAGCUGGAGUGUACCUUUUCAUGAUCAUCUGGCAGCUGACUGAGUUGAAUACCUUCUUCUUGAAGCAUAUCUUUGUGUUCCAAGCCAGUCAUCCAUUAAGUUGGGGUAGAAUUCUCUUUAUUGGUGGCAUCACAGCUCCCACAGUGAGACAGUACUACGCUUACCUCACCGACACACAGUGCAAGCGCGUAGGAACACAAUGCUGGGUGUUUGGGGUCAUUGGUUUCCUGGAGGCCAUUGUUUGCAUAAAAUUUGGACAAGAUCUCUUCUCUAAGACCCAAAUACUCUAUGUUGUGCUUUGGCUUCUUUGCGUGGCUUUCACCACUUUCCUCUGUCUGUACGGCAUGAUUUGGUAUGCAGAACACUAUGGUCACCGAGAAAAGACCUACUCGGAGUGUGAAGAUGGCACCUACAGUCCAGAGAUCUCCUGGCAUCACAGGAAAGGGACAAAAGGUUCUGAAGACAGCCCACCCAAGCAUGCAGGCAACAACGAAAGCCAUUCUUCCAGGAGAAGGAAUCGGCAUUCCAAGUCAAAAGUCACCAAUGGCGUUGGAAAGAAAUGAAAAACCCUGGUUAAUCAAAGAUGUUCCAGAGUGCCUAGAACUGAGAGGGAAAUGGAACUCAUUUGGAACUCCCCGUGAGGAGGUCGAGGCGCACAGGGCAAGCAGGAAGAGGCGAGGGCACUUGGGGGUCAUUAUUUGAGAUCGUAAGUCUUGUUUCCCACAGACCUGGCCGCGUCAGGCAGAUCAUCGCCUGGGGGGCCUUUGCCAACGUGGGGUCUCUUCUAACUUCAGCACUUGACAUGCGGUCACCGGUGGCAGCGCGGUGUGUUGAAGGGAAACGGUAGCUAUUCAUUCACAGUUGCCAAGAGCAGCUCCGCGCCUGCUGGAUCGUGGAUGCAGCGUAAACAUCUUCCUUCAGACGAGGCAUUAACCCCAUGGUUAAUGGACUGGUCACCAGUUUUUAUUUUAUUUUUAUGAAUCUACCUUUCCAUUGAUUGAUUUAAGUUCAGGCCACUUUUCUGUCUUUUAUUUGGUUACUGUUGUUAUUUGUUUUUAAGUUAGGAUGCUUUUUAACAGCCUUUAGAAGCCGCUGCUGAAAUUGAUACUGGGGGAAGGGUUCCCCUUCCUUCUAGAGCAGAAAAGGGAGAGAGGUGUUGUAUUCCUGUUUGGUAACCUCAGUCUCCUGUAAGACCUCCUACCACAUGGCGAGUAUACACCAAUCAGGAGAGGGUAGCUGCCUGCAUAGGAGCCUCGCUUCCGAUUAUUCCCUUCCCAAUAUUAUUCAUCCAGACUUAGCCACAGUGCACAAAAGCAAACCUGCUAGAGAGGCAGUGAACACCACAGCUUCUCCCCAGCUAGGUGCCUUUUACAUCGGGUUUGUUCUCCUUCCAUGGUGUGUUGCUGACAUUGUCACUGAGUCCCAUGUGAGGUGCUGGUGAGUAUUACCUUUCAUCUGUGCCAUGCUCUAGAACCUUGACCUUGAUAGUUCACCACCUCUGAUGGAUCCCUGUUUUAAAUAAAAACGAUUCACUUUAAAGCCUAUCAAAGGUCUGUCUGUAAAAUGCUCAUUUUCUUGCAUCUUACUGGUAUCUUCUAUUGAUUGUAAGCAGUCUGUGUUUUUCAAGUGACUUUAGGAUAAUAUAUAUGUGUUUUACAUAGUGAGAAGAAAAAAGAAAAGAUGUGUAUUUUAAAGGGCUUACAGACAUAUAUGUCCUACUUCUUAGACUACCCAAGUGACCAACAGGAAUGAACAACAUAGUCAUUGUUUUUUCCUGUGGUAAUGGUUUCCAAGUUGGACUUUUUUUUCCUCUAACAAGAGGCCAGUACCCAGUUGAUUAGCUUACAGAUAUCAACUCACUGAAAGUAAUCUUUUGUUCCCUCAUUUCACACAGCACAAAGGUUCGUUCUGAUGUUUCUUCUUCUUUAAGGAAAUCUUUAGCCAUAGAAGUGUCACUUUUUUUUUUUCUGCAAAAGAAUUCCAAGAUGAACGGGUUGAAUGAAUCAUGCCAGCCAGGGUCACAUCCUGUCCUCAGGGGGCCCAGUGCUCAAUAGUAGAUUCUGCGGGAGUGGAGAAGCGUCAGUGGCAGCUCCGCUCACUUGGUGAGUGAGGGAUUUGGCUGUGAUGAGCCUCAGCUCCGAGCUCUCAAAUGUCCUCCAGCCAGCAUCUGCCUGCUUCCCACAAAAGGAUAGAAGAGAGGCAAAGUGCGUGUUUCAUAAAACCUGCCUGCACUUUUAUAACCCAUCAAAGAGGCCAUUUUUAAACACAGGUACAAUUUAAACAUGAUCUUUCUUUGCAAAUAAAUAUGUUUUGUUUCAUCCUGUGUUCUGCUUUUCUAAGCAUGACAUACUUGUGCCCAUUGGAGAAGACACCUGUCUCUUCUUUCUCACACCGGUGGUGCCUCACUGAGUGUUUCCGGGUUCAUUUUCCGGGAGCACUGGGCCUGACACUUUCACACUCUUCUGACUUUCGCCUUGUUGCAACUGAUGGAGCAUGUGUGCUUCCUCUGAGGCCAGCCUACAGGAGGCAGCUGUUUCGCAGGUGGUGAAUUCGACUUUACUGUGGCAUUGUGAAGAGCAGGGUGCACAGGAGAUGAUUUUUUCUCCAUGGCUUUGUAAGAAACAGCCAGGAAAGUUCUCAGAUACUUUCCAUGCCCUUUCUUUGAGUUGAAACUUUCUAUUUCCCUUCAGUCAGAGCUCUUUACUAUAGUAGUUACAAAACCAGUGCUUUCCAUGGCUGGCCAGAACCACAGCUGCUAUUCCUUUUAGAAGCCAUACUGCUGGGUUUGGCCUACUUUUUUCACCGUUUCUAUGGAAAUAAACCUCACAUUGAUGGAAAUAGAAUGCGUGUUUCAGAAUCAUCAUUCAAUAUCUGAAAUGAUUUGAUUGUAAAUUAUCUCAUGGUCCCUGUUUGCAAACCACCCUCUUAAGAGAGAACAUUGUUUUGGACCUAAAGCUUGAAGAACGGUUUAUGUAUUUUUCUCCUUAAGUAGCAUUGCAUUGAGUGUUAGGUUCUUUUCCCUUUUUUUCAUUCUUGGUCUUCCCAAAGCUUCUUCCCACAUUUCGUUUGUGUCUGUUUCCACCAUUCAUAGAAACCUUGGAACCACUCUCACAGCAAUGCUAGGAUGUUUCAUGGACCUGUUAAGCAUUUUGAUGAUACAAGACAUCCUAUCAAUGCCAGUCUUAUUUUCGCUAGGACUCUGCUUCCACAGUAAGCUCCUAAGGUGCUCACCCAACCCAGGAGAAAACAAAAUUCAUUACCAAAUACAACAGGUUCAGCCUUCUUGGUCUUCCCUCAGAAGCCACCGUGUAGCACCCUGGAAUGAUGCCUCUUUAUGCCAAGGCCCACCCUUUGGAAUUGGGAGGGUUUUGGGUAGAAUCCUGCACUUACAGAGGCCCUUGGGGUCAUUGAGAAGUGGAGGAGGUUGGACACAGAAGGGGAGGCUAAACACAAGGUGGGGAAGAAAAAAUGUAACCAUUGGCAGCCAGACUGAAGCUAGCCCUUUAAAAUACGGGGUUGGGGGGUUAACAUCCGCUCUUUGGAAUGUGCUCAGUGACUGCUGCAGAGUUCCUGGGCCACCCUAAUGUUUACCAGGUGGGCGUUGUUUAUAUGGUUCUUAUUGUUAUGACAACUAGAAAUCCCACAGUAGACUAGACAGUGCUCCCUACCAUUUCCCAUUUAUAGGAUUGAAAUCAAGAUGUAAGGAGAGCUGGCCGGGCGCAGGGCUCACGCCUGUAAUCCCAGCACUUUGGGAGGCUGAGGUGGGUGGAUCGCCUGAGGUCAGGAGUUUGAGACCAGCCUGACCAAUAUGGUGAAACCCUGUCUCUGCUGAAAAUACUUAAAUUAGCCGGGCAUGGUGGCAGGCACCUGUAGUCCCAGCUACUCGGGAGACAGAGACAGAAGAAAUGCUUGAACCCAGGAGGUGGAGGUUCCAGUGAGCCGAGAUCACGCCACCGCACUCUCUAACCUGGGCGACAGAGCGAGACUAUCUC